AGUUGCCGGAGCCCGUUCUGGUCUCAAGUAGGAAGCUAGUGCGCUGUAACCGCAUCUGAUCUGGGCGCUCCGGGAAGGGCGAGACUGGAGCAGAGCCGCUGGGCGCCGGAGCCGAGGCGAGCGCCGCGCGCACCACUGACAGGGAAACUGAAACUUCCCAGGCUGUGCAGCUAGUAGGUGGGACUUGGACCCAGACCAGGUUGGAGUUGCUGUGGGUGAGCUGCUGUGGUCUGUAGCCAAGCAUGCUGUGGUCGGAUCUGCCCAGCCGUGGAACAGAAACAUUUGCUGGAUGGAAAAUCCAUAAAAGAAAGCUCCUGUGAAAAGCUGAGGCUGACAAUAAUUUAAGCAAAAUCAGAUCGAUCUCUUUGGGCUGCCUGACCUCCUUGGGUGCUUGCUAUUAAUUAACAGACUUUGUGGGGAAAAAAAGGAGCUUGCCUUCUGAGCUUUGUACCAAAGACCUGGGAAAACUAACCAUCUCAGUCUUUCCUGAGGACUUGGGAACUGCCGAGGCCUCUGCCAAUGUGUUGACUGUCGCUAUGGGCUCACUGUUGUCCAGGCAGCUCAUAUUUCAAAUUAUAACCUAUUUCCUGCACCAUUGCUGACGCCUGGUGAUCCAUGUCAGAAGUACUUCCAGCUGACUCAGGUGUUGACACCUUGGCAGUGUUUAUGGCCAGCAGCGGAACUACAGACGUCACAAAUCGGAACAGCCCAGCCACACCACCAAACACCCUUAACCUCCGAUCCUCCCACAAUGAACUGUUGAACGCUGAAAUAAAACACACAGAAACCAAGAACAGCACACCUCCCAAAUGCAGGAAAAAAUAUGCACUAACUAACAUCCAGGCGGCCAUGGGCCUCUCGGAUCCAGCUGCACAGCCCCUGCUGGGAAAUGGCUCUGCCAACAUCAAGCUGGUGAAAAAUGGGGAGAACCAGCUCCGUAAGGCUGCAGAGCAAGGGCAGCAGGACCCCAACAAAAACCUGAGCCCCACUGCAGUCAUCAACAUAACUUCUGAGAAGUUAGAGGGUAAAGAGCCCCACCCACAGGAUUCCUCGAGCUGUGAGAUUUUACCCUCCCAGCCCAGGAGAACUAAGAGCUUCCUAAAUUACUAUGCAGAUCUGGAAACCUCAGCCAGAGAACUAGAGCAGAACCGAGGCAAUCACCAUGGGACUGCGGAAGAGAAAUCCCAGCCAGUCCAGGGCCAGGCCUCCACCAUCAUUGGGAAUGGCGAUUUGCUGCUGCAGAAACCAAACAGACCCCAGUCCAGCCCUGAAGACGGCCAAGUAGCCACAGUGUCAUCCAGCCCAGAAACCAAGAAGGAUCAUCCGAAAACAGGGGCCAAAACCGACUGUGCACUGCACCGGAUCCAGAACCUGGCACCGAGCGAUGAGGAGUCCAGCUGGACAACGUUGUCCCAAGACAGUGCCUCACCCAGCUCCCCGGAUGAAACAGCAGAUAUAUGGAGUGAUCACUCAUUUCAGACUGAUCCAGAUUUGCCGCCUGGCUGGAAAAGAGUCAGUGACAUUGCCGGGACCUAUUAUUGGCACAUCCCAACAGGAACGACUCAGUGGGAACGGCCCGUCUCCAUCCCAGCAGAUCUCCAGGGUUCUAGGAAAGGGUCACUUAGUUCUGUAACGCCAUCUCCCACCCCAGAGAACGAGAAACAGCCAUGGAGUGAUUUUGCUGUUCUGAAUGGGGGAAAGAUUAAUAGUGACAUUUGGAAGGAUUUGCAUGCAGCCACUGUUAACCCGGACCCCAGUUUAAAAGAGUUUGAAGGAGCAACCCUACGCUAUGCAUCUUUGAAACUCAGAAAUGCCCCACACCCUGAUGAUGAUGAUUCUUGUAGUAUCAACAGUGACCCAGAAGCCAAGUGUUUUGCUGUGCGUUCUCUGGGAUGGGUAGAGAUGGCAGAAGAGGACCUCGCCCCCGGUAAAAGUAGUGUUGCGGUCAACAACUGCAUCAGGCAACUUUCCUACUGCAAAAAUGACAUCCGAGACACAGUCGGGAUUUGGGGAGAGGGGAAAGACAUGUACCUGAUCCUGGAGAAUGACAUGCUCAGCCUGGUGGACCCCAUGGACCGCAGCGUGCUGCACUCGCAGCCCAUCGUCAGCAUCCGCGUGUGGGGCGUGGGCCGCGACAAUGGCCGAGAGAGGGAUUUUGCUUAUGUAGCAAGAGAUAAAGAUACAAGAAUUUUGAAAUGUCAUGUAUUUCGAUGUGACACACCAGCAAAAGCCAUUGCCACAAGUCUCCACGAGAUCUGCUCCAAGAUUAUGGCUGAACGGAAGAAUGCCAAAGCGCUGGCCUGCAGCUCCUUACAGGAAAGGGCCAAUGUGAACCUCGAUGUCCCUUUGCAAGUAGAUUUUCCAACACCAAAGACUGAGCUGGUCCAGAAGUUCCACGUGCAGUACUUGGGCAUGUUACCUGUAGACAAACCAGUCGGAAUGGAUAUUUUGAACAGUGCCAUAGAAAAUCUUAUGACCUCAUCCAACAAGGAGGACUGGCUGUCAGUGAACAUGAACGUGGCUGAUGCCACUGUGACUGUCAUCAGUGAAAAGAAUGAAGAGGAAGUCUUAGUGGAAUGUCGUGUGCGAUUCCUGUCCUUCAUGGGUGUUGGGAAGGACGUCCACACAUUUGCCUUCAUCAUGGACACGGGGAACCAGCGCUUUGAGUGCCACGUUUUCUGGUGCGAGCCUAAUGCUGGUAACGUGUCUGAGGCGGUGCAGGCCGCCUGCAUGUUACGAUAUCAGAAGUGCUUGGUAGCCAGGCCGCCUUCUCAGAAAGUUCGACCACCUCCACCGCCAGCAGAUUCAGUAACCAGAAGAGUCACAACCAAUGUAAAACGAGGGGUCUUAUCCCUCAUUGACACUUUGAAACAGAAACGCCCUGUCACCGAAAUGCCAUAGCUGCACAUGCAAAAGGACUCGGCUAUUUACCUGAAGAUUGACUAGCUACACUAAAGAAAAUGAACUCCGCCAUCCGACCUUCCAUCCAGUUGCUGAUGCUUUGUCUUCAGAGAAUUUACCCUUAACCAAGCAGUGUUAGACAAGCAUGUUCUCUCGUCUUGCCACCAUCAUGUGAUAUGAAAAGAAGCAUGAAUAAUUUUUUUUGCUGUAAGUUACAUCAUGCGCAGUGGAAGGUCUUUUUCUUAUUGUAAAUAUUGUGAACAUUACUUAACUUCACACACACACAGAGAAGAGUGUGGCCCCACCCCUCCUAGUGAACUAACGCUGCGUCCUUGGAAUGAAUGAUGCGUGAGUUAGUUUCACUGUCUUCUUGGCUGGACCUGUCACAAGCAACCUUUAAGUCCUACAGCACUUUGCCCUGUUUUCAACAUUGGAGUAGGCACUGCAUAGCAGAUACCAUUGAAUUGCUGUAAAAAUAGGAUGGCGAGUUUGUGUUUUAAUUUUUCAUAAAAUUGAACCUGUUGGUUGACAAAAUUGGCUGUUGGCAUCAGUAUAGAAACCAACUGGCAGCUUUCCCUGACAAGCUCUUUGACACAUGGACACCAUUUCAUGUCUACAGCUGUUUGUGGGAUGUUGGAAAAAAAUGAAACUUCAAAAUUGAUGAAAAACUAAAUUCGAGGAAUUAAAAUCGAACAAAACAUAGCCUUUCUUUUCCGAUGGUUUUCAAACUGAUUAUUUUUAAAAGAGAUUAAUAAAAUCAUAAUGCAUUUUGGGUGGGACAUAUUUCAAACUUCUGCCUUAUAUUGUACGGUGCAGCUAGAGAAUUAUAGUUCACUAUGGCCAUUCUCUACAUAAACAUUAAGAUGAAAUACUCCUCAUCAGCCUUUCAUCCUUAGUUUGAGAAUUAGCUGAUAUGCAAUUUGAAGUUGAGGAAAUAUCAUUGAUAUUUCUAUCAUGCACGAUUAUUUUAGAUUUCUACCACCGUGUGAUUUUUGCUAGUCCAUGUGCUAGAGGUAAACGUUCUGCUGGAAUUCUGCAUCCAGCUCUAUCCCCCUCUGAUGCUUUUUGCCCAGAAAGCUGUCUGUCCAUCAUGUAUUGUCCAUGGCAACAAAUUACAUUAGGUUGAACCUUUCCUUGAUUUUAUGUAUUUAAUAUUAGAAUUUGUUGGACUCAACUAGAUAUAUUUUUUAAUUUAUAUUUUUUCCAUUUUACUUUGAAGAUUUGAAAUGUUCAUACCUGAGCAAAGUCUACACAGGAGUAAUGGACUGUUUAACAAGUUUCCCAAAACAGCAUUUUCCUGCUCCUUCGUAUGUAGGUGAGAAACUUAGCUGGAAAGACAUACAAAUUUAGACUCUCGUUGACAUUGUCGUUUUAAAAGGAAGUUGCUAAGGCGAUCAAUCUCAAUAUUAGUCUUGUUUACUUCUUCUUAAUGUCAAAAUUAACAUUUACAACAUCCAAUUAUAAAAGUAAUGCUUUAUGUUUAUACACUGCUAUGUACUUGUCAAAAUGGUUUCCACAUUCUUAUCACAUCUGAGCCUUACCAGGUAGAGAAGGUACUAAAUACACUUUAGAAGUAAAAAUAUGAAGUACCGAGAGGCUAAACCCACUGGCCUAAGAUCUCACCAAAGUUCAUGAAAACCAGGACUAGGACCCACGGCUCCCAAAGCCCGUUCUUGCUGUGUUGUGCUGCCUCCAUAUCCGUCAGGAAGAGCCUUUCCAGAAUGAUUCUGGGCAUAUACUAAGAAGAGCAGGUAUGGAAAGAUCUAUUGUCAGGGAAUCUUAGAAUUCCCUACACGAGUGGGAGAAAGAUGUCCAAAUUCCUUACGCAGUGGUAUUCAUGAUGGUGCCCUAUCUAAGUCCAGGACUGUUUUCCUACAGCGUGCCUCAAAAGUGUUGUAGAGGGCAGGAUUCUACAUUCACAGCCUGUUCCAUCUACGAGAUUUUCCAGAUGCUACUUGUGGUAGACAUUCCUAACUCAUGGUACUUAGCCACCAGAGAUCAUGAUGGAAUGAGUGGGUGGCUUUUCUACCUGCCAUUCCCUCAGAAUUCAUGAGGGGUGGGGGACAGGGGGACCGGAAUUGUCUUAGCACCCCAAUGUUAUGACAAAACUAUGCUACUUUAGAAACGCAGUCUGUUUUUCACCAAUUGACAUACUACUGAUCUGAAGUAACCAGUGCCAUCAUAAGAAAUUACUGCAUUAAGAAAAUCCUUGCUGUGCCCUUUGAAAAGCUGUUCAGAAAUCAUUUACAGUGAUCUUUCAUCUCGGUCGCUGUAGUGAAACAUUUUAGUGUGAUAAAUUUCAAAAUUCUAAACAAAUUACCCACUUUUAUAUUGGAAAUCUCUACCAGAACUCCCUCUUCAUUUUUUAAGGCAUACAUUUGCUUGUUUUCAAGAUCAAGAAUUCUGAGCUAGCUUUAAGUAGCAAACUGAUUUAUAUGUGCAAUUAUAGGAUGCAUUAAGAUGAAUGAUAGCCUUUACAUAUUGAAAACUUUGCAGACGUUUUGUUUUGAAAAUGGCAUUGUAUAGUAAAUGCAAAUUAAUUUUGUAAAAUUAUGUUAAAGAGUAUGUUCAGACACUUUCUGCCAUGGCCAAAAAGUAUGUAUGAAAGUAUGUGUGUAUUUGUUUGUAAAAGGAUGCCAAUGUUUUACCUGAUAUCUUAGUGACACUUCAGUUAUCUAUGCAUUCUUUAGAUCUGUGAUUCGGUAAACAGGCAGCCAUGUUCACGAUGCCUUCUAUGUCUUACCAUAUUUUUAAUUAACCUGUUAAAUACAGCUUAAAAUAUUUUUAUUUUAUUUAUUCUAUUUUUACUGAAAUAUACUGCAUUAUUGUGUUAAUGUAUUAUCUUUCCUGGAUAUUAUCUCCCAGUGUAUCCAGAUCUAAGUAAUCUCAGUGAACUAUACAUUGCCUAAAAAGUGGUUUUGUAAUGAUUUGUAGUCACAUUUCUAUUGGGAUAUGUAGAAGAAAAGGCAAAAUGCUUAAAGUUCCUUUUAUUUUUUAAAAGCAGCUAGAUAGACACAGACUUGCCACCUCAUACAUCUGCUCCUUGGCAACAUCAAGGGGAACGACUAGCCAACAUGCCUAUGGCUAAAAACUUUCCUUUGCAGACUAAAGCACUGCUUGGUGCUUCGUUUUUCUACCCUUCACAACAUGUGUGAUUUCAUCUAAGAGAUAUAUACAUGUACACAUGCCCUUUGUUUCCACCUGGAUACAAGAUCACUCAUAGCUAAUUAGGACCAUUGUUUUUUGUUCAUCUGUCUUGUUGCAUGAAGGGACAUUAGACCCAUUUCCAUUAAAAUAAGUUCUUGGUGAUAAACUGUGGCACUGCUACUUCUUUUUAAAUCCACUUUAUGAUUUCAAGAUGGACACUUGUAAGAUGACUCGACACAAGGCCAUUGCCUGGAAGCCCCAGAGCUUUCCUCUGUUUGUAUGGCCCGUUCAUGUCCCAGGCAUUGCAACACAAACUCCUCAAGAUUUCACCACAACAUGACAAGCAUUUUCCUAACUGAUAUUAGCACAAUUUAACUAAUAAGCCCCUUCGCUCUCUAGUUGGCCAGGCUUAACCUAAUACACAUCUAACGUGUGUGCCACACGGCCAGUAGAAAGUUUAACUUCAGCUUCAGGGCAAAGAUACCCACUCACACCGUGUCAACGCAAGCAGUAGUUCCUGGCCUCCAGAGCAGCUUACUUCCCCUGAAAGAACGCUUUGUUUUCCUUUAUGCCCUUUUCCUGUUGACCACUUUUACACAUUUAAAUGUAAUUUGUUGUGAGAAUAAAUUUAGCUGCAUAAAACGUUCGGCUCAUUUAUCUGACAUCUUAGUCACAUAUACAAGGAAUAGAAAUAGAAACUCGGUGUCUCUAGUUAUUUUUAAAUUAUUCUUACCUCAGACUUCUUAGAAAUCACUUUAGUAAUGGAGCAUUUUGCUUUGAUUAGUUACUACAUAUUUCUGCCUGGUAAGAACUAGGAAGUAACUUCAAAUUUUGAGUAAUCACCCUGUACUUAUUUGGUGAUCAGGAAGGCCAGCUGGCCUUCCGGACAUAGAAGCCUAUUUAGUCACCAACUCGAGUCUUUUGUAAGCGGUCUUGCUAGGAUUGUGAUAUUUUAGCACGAAGAAGUUUAUCACUUCCUUUAAGAACCUGACAUCAAAGAAUAAAGAAUAGAGGUGUACACACACUAAAUCCAAAAUGAAAGGUAACUAGAGAAAUCAGUUGAAUCUGGUUUAGCUUAACUGUUAGGCGCAGGAAGGCAGAUAAACAGAAUUUAAAGUAUGUCCCCGCUUUUUGUUCAUCUUGCACUUCCACAGUGGUUUCUCUCUAGUCAGUAACAAAAUUUCAUUAUGGUUUCAGGCAUUAUAUGGUGGUAAAUAAUUUCAGAUUAAAAAUGUGUUUGCUAUUGGAGUAUCUGAAUACUAGUAAUUUCAUUAUUUAGAAUUUUGCAGCACUUUUAUCUCAAGAAGAAGUCCAAGAAUGUAAAAUGCCAAAUGAAACAUGUCAGUGGAAUCAAUAUUCUCCUUCAUUAGAAUUCCCUCAUAUUGCUUUUUUUUUUUUUCUUCAGACAGAGGAGUCUUACUCUGGAGUGCAGUGGUGUAAUUUCAGCUCACCACAACCUCCACCUCCCAAGUUCAAGCAAUUCUCGCCUCAGCCUCCUGAGUAGCUGGGAUUACAGGCAUGCACCGCCACGCCUGGCCAAUUUGUAUAUUUUUAGUAGAGACAGGGUUUCGCCACGUUGGCCAGGCUGGUCUCGAACUCCUGACCUCAGGUGAUCCGCCCGCCCCAACCUCCCAAAGUAUGUGAGCCACCACGUCCGGCCUCAUAUUGCUUUUAUCCAAAAUUCUUUUCCCUUUUCACUCUACCAAAGUAUUUAAAUAAUCCUGUCCUUCAUAGAAGAUUCUCAAAGAAGAAAACUGCAGUGUAAUUAAUGAAUGGUUUAAUUCAGAAUCUUCAUAUACUUCUAAAGAGAAAAAUAAUUUAGUGCCAAAUGCAUGUUAGGAGAUAAUCAAUGUAAGUGGCAACAAAUUGUGACUUCACAUGCUACUGUAGAGAUCAGAAAAUUAUCCUAAACUAUUCCAUAACAAUGAGACAACAUCACAGAAAAUACACUUGAAAAUAAAAAUCUCAAGACCAGCUACUUCUGGACAAUGGAAUACUUUUCAGUCUGGUAUGGUGGAGGGCCCGAAAAGGAUAAGGGAUUCUUAUGAUACACAAUGGGAUUCUUUACUGAACAAUAUGUUAAAUUAAGCUGCACCGCCUUCCUUGAGGCAUGGACUACCCUAACCAACCAGAUAGAAAUCUGGGUGGGAUAAGAGGAUGAGCCACACGCUAUAAUUUUAGGGCAAGGAGAUAGUGUUUGAUUUUCAAAAUCAGCAAAAUAAGCUGAGCACUUUAUAUCUUUCUGUACAAGAGUGAUAACAUGAAGAAUUCUUCUUCAGGGAUUUAAAAUACAAUAAGCCUGGUUCAACUAUAAAAAGUCUUGUUUCCUUUCUUCAUUGACACUUUUUUUUUUUUUUUUUUUUUUUUGAGGCAAGGUCUCACUCUGCUUCCCAGGCUGGAGUGCAGUGGGGCAAUAUUGGCUCACUGCAACCUGCACCUCCUGGACUCAAGAGAUCCUCGUACCUCAGCCUCCUAAGUAGCUGGGACUACAGGCGUGUCCCACCACACCCAGCUAAUUUUUGUAUUUUUUGUAGAGAUGGGGUUUUGGGGUUUCGCCAUGUUGUCCAGGCUCGUCUGGAACUCCGGUGCUCAAGUGGCGUGCCCACCUCAGCCUCCCAAACUGCUGAGAUUACAGAUGUGAGCCACUGCACCCAGCCCACUGACACGUUUUACUGAUAAAUGUAAAUCUAAGCUAAAAUAAAAAUAAUGUAUUACCGCUAUAAUACAAUUCACCAUUCUCUUUUCUCACUUCAAGUAAGAAAGUAAAAAUAGAAUAUCAGAGCUGAAGUAGACCUAAGUAUUCAUCUUGAAGAAGAUAAUAUUCUAAAAAUCAUGCCACCUGAAUUGAGCAUUUAGGAAUUUAUGUAACAUUUCUAUACAACUGAAUUGCAAAAAUAAAACUUUAAAUUCAAACUUUA